AAGCGUUUCCCCCGCCCGGCUUCAUCCCUGCUGGCGGCCCAGCGUCGUUCUCCUCCUGCGCGAGGCGGCCAAGGCCUGCUGGCCCGGAGCCGCGCCUCCACCCGCGCGAGGUAGGGCUUCGAGGACCGGCGCGGCGCAGGUCUCCGGAGGCCUCCCGAGAGGGGCUAGGGUCGCCGGGCCGCGCGUGGGAGCGGGUGGGGCCCGGGAGGAGACGGCGCCCCGGAGGGGAGUGCGAGGCCUGGGCCGACGGUUACGGGCGCCGACCGGCGUUGCCUGGCCUGAACGCCCGGCCUUUCGGUGGAGGGCAGCUUGCCCCUGUAUGUUGCGCCCUUCCGUGGGUCAGACCGGCGGCAAGGUAUCGUCCUUGGAGAAGAUGGAAGCGGAGAGGCGGCCGGCGCCGGGCUCGCCCUCCGAGGGCCUGUUUGCGGACGGGCACCUGAUCUUGUGGACGCUGUGCUCGGUCCUGCUGCCGGUGUUCAUCACCUUCUGGUGUAGCCUCCAGCGGUCGCGCCGGCAGCUGCACCGCAGGGACAUCUUCCGCAAGAGCAAGCACGGGUGGCGCGACACGGACCUGUUCAGCCAGCCCACCUACUGCUGCGUGUGCGCGCAGCACAUUCUGCAGGGCGCCUUCUGCGACUGCUGCGGGCUCCGCGUGGACGAGGGCUGCCUCAGGAAGGCCGACAAGCGCUUCCAGUGCAAGGAGAUUAUGCUCAAGAAUGACACCAAGGUCCUGGACGCCAUGCCCCACCACUGGAUCCGGGGCAACGUGCCCCUGUGCAGUUACUGUAUGGUUUGCAAGCAGCAGUGUGGCUGUCAACCCAAGCUUUGCGAUUACAGGUGCAUUUGGUGCCAGAAAACAGUACAUGAUGAGUGCAUGAAAAAUAGUUUAAAGAAUGAAAAAUGUGAUUUUGGAGAAUUCAAAAACCUAAUCAUUCCACCAAGUUAUUUAACAUCCAUUAAUCAGAUGCGUAAAGACAAAAAAACAGAUUAUGAAGUGCUAGCCUCUAAGCUUGGAAAGCAGUGGACCCCAUUAAUAAUCCUGGCCAACUCUCGUAGUGGAACUAAUAUGGGAGAAGGACUGUUGGGAGAAUUUAGGAUCUUGUUGAAUCCAGUCCAGGUUUUUGAUGUAACUAAAACUCCUCCUAUCAAAGCCCUACAACUCUGUACUCUUCUCCCAUAUUAUUCAGCUCGAGUACUUGUUUGUGGAGGGGAUGGGACUGUAGGGUGGGUCCUGGAUGCAGUUGAUGACAUGAAGAUUAAGGUAUUAGUCUUUAAGAACUACUACAGAAGGACUUCUAAGAUAAAUAUACUAUACAUAUAUAUAUAUAUAUGGGUUUUGUUGUUGUUUUGUUGUUGUUGUUGUUUUUUCUUGAGAUACAGUCUCGCACUGUCACCCAGGCUGGAGUGCAGCGGCGCAGACACAGCUAACUGCAACCUCCAUUUCUCAGGUUCAAGCCAUCCUCCCACCUCAGCCUACAAAGUUGCUGAGACUAUAGGUGUGCGCUACCAUGCCUGGCUAAUUUUUGUAUUUUUUGUAGAGACAGGGUUUCACCAUGUUGCCUGGGCUGCUGUCAAACUCCUGGGCUCAAGCGAUCCUCCCACCUUGGCCUCCCAAAGUGCUGGGAUUACAUGGGGACAAGAAAAGUACAUUCCACAAGUUGCAGUUUUGCCUCUGGGAACAGGCAACGAUCUAUCCAAUACAUUGGGUUGGGGUACAGGUUAUGCUGGAGAAAUUCCAGUUGCGCAGGUUUUGCGAAAUGUAAUGGAAGCAGAUGGAAUUAAACUAGAUCGAUGGAAAGUUCAAGUAACAAAUAAAGGAUACUACAACUUAAGAAAACCCAAGGAAUUCACAAUGAACAACUAUUUUUCUGUUGGACCUGAUGCUCUCAUGGCUCUCAAUUUUCAUGCUCAUCGUGAGAAGGCACCAUCUCUGUUUUCUAGCAGAAUUCUUAAUAAGGCGGUUUACUUAUUCUAUGGAACCAAAGAUUGUUUAGUGCAAGAAUGUAAAGAUUUGAAUAAAAAAGUUGAGCUAGAACUGGAUGGUGAGCGAGUAGCACUGCCCAGCUUGGAAGGUAUUAUAGUUCUGAACAUCGGAUACUGGGGCGGUGGCUGCAGACUAUGGGAAGGGAUGGGGGACGAGACUUACCCUCUAGCCAGGCAUGACGAUGGUCUGCUGGAAGUCGUUGGAGUAUAUGGGUCUUUCCACUGUGCUCAGAUUCAAGUAAAACUGGCUAAUCCUUUUCGAAUAGGACAGGCACAUACAGUGAGGCUGAUUUUGAAGUGCUCCAUGAUGCCAAUGCAGGUGGAUGGGGAGCCUUGGGCCCAAGGGCCCUGCACUGUCACCAUAACUCACAAGACACAUGCAAUGAUGUUAUAUUUCUCUGGAGAACAAACAGAUGAUGACAUCUCUAGUACUUCGGAUCAAGAAGAUAUAAAGGCGACUGAAUAGAUGGAUGAGGGAGUGAAAACUUUGCAUAGAAUCCUCACGCAAGUAGAUACAUGUUCAUCCAAAAGUAUUAAUAGAAAUUCUCUAUCAGCUAUUCAGUCUUAAUUUCACUAGUAGUAUAAUGGGUAUACAUUUUUGUAAAUAGCAUCCCCAAACCAGCCAGCCUUCAGUUAUUUACAAAUGUUUGUUCUUUUUUCAGCAAAAUACUUCAAAUGAAUAGUAUUAACUUACAAAAAGUCACAAAAACUUACAUGAGAGUGAAAAUUUGUUAUGACUGUUUUGAGAGUGGGACUCACUCUGAAGUAUGUGCUGUCUCAUGUCUUAUUUUUGAACCAUGCAUAUGAUGGACACACAAUGGAUGGACACAUUAUAUCUCCAACAAGGUGUGGGUGGAAAGAUCAAAUUAACCUGCUUUUUUGAAAGGAAAUGAUUACUGUCAAACCAGCAUGGUUAAUUGUGAGCAUCCUCCUGCAGCAUGCCCCUUAAGAUUUUCUACAACCCAAACCAAGUGUAUGUAUUGAUUUCUAGGAACCCCCAAAAGGAGAAUAGUAAAAAAAGAUCAUACUUAAAAUUUGUAUUACAAUUUUUAUUUUAGGAACUUAUUCAGACACGUAAAUGUUGUUUAAUUCUGUAGGUAACCAUUUGAGCUGCAAUUCAGGAUCUUUUUUAUAACACCAGUGUAGCCAAAAGAGAAACAGAUAAGUGAAUUGGUAAGAAAUAAGAUUCAGAGCACUUGGGAUUGUAAGUUAUAGGUUCUGAGCUGAACUGUUUAUCAGCCGCUCUUUUUAUUAAAAGACAGUGUCAACACUUCAAAAAACGUGCUUAAAGGAGACAACGGUGAGAUUAAUUGCUUAGAAAAAGCUCAAGGCUGACUGAUAAGUUUUAAAAAUUUGGUGGUCUUGUAGUAUUUUGAAAUACAGUAGUCUUUUAACAGAAUUUCCCCUUAGGGAGGUAAGUGGACAGAAAUCUUUGCUAAAAUGUUUAUAUCAUAUUUAUUUUAAAAUGAGAGAGAUAUAUUUUUAAAUUAUUUAUUAUUUACCUUGUGGUAUGGUACCUGUGUUUAGUGUUUACGUUCUGUAGCUUUAUUUAAUAAGUUAAAUUGAUCACAUAAAUUCUGCUAGUCACAAUCAGAUAGAAAUUUAGUCUAUUAAUUAAAAUUCUAAUUUAAUUCUCCUGACAGAAAUCUAGAUAUUCUUAUUCUUCACAAAUAUUCCUCAUUGUAUUGAAAAAUGAAGGAGGGCAUGAAAAGCACUAGGGAACUACUUUUGGAUAACUGAAAGCUUUGUUUCAUUGUUUUAUUUGCCCCUCAAUUGCCACAAACUUACUGAAGGGCUAGUUUCAUGGUUCCCAUUAGAGGGUGCUUGUUCGCUGCUGUUGACCAGCCCAAGGGUCGUGACCCACAGGUCGGCUGACCCAGAGGGCAUCCAGCCUGGUGUUUUUCUGACACAUGGCCCAGGCUUUGUGGUCUUUCAUGACAUUAAUCUCUGAAAGAUCAGAAUGUAUCCCCCAAAAUACCAUUAGCUAUCUUUGAGGGUCUAUUAUGAAUCUGUCAUCCAUGAAUUGCCAUAAACCUAAGUUUGCCUCACCUCAGGCCCAGACCAUGUUUUCAAAGAGCAACUUAGUAAUGUAUACAGUAGUCAGUACAUUUUAUGAAAUACUCUAUUUUGCUAAAUUAACCUCUUGCAGAUCUCCUCAGGUGAUCUUAAAUUCUAGUCUUGAGAAACUUUGUGAGCAGAUCUGUUUUCAGCUUCUUUAUAUACCUUUCAUGGUAAGUAACCAUGGCAGUGAGGAUGGCAGAGUUUUGUUUUUUUUUUUUUUAAUGGGCCAAUCAUGUUCUGAGUAUUAUGAAGUUUAUCCUUUCAUUCAUGAUCAAAAUUGUUAAAGACAUCACAUUUUAUAAAUACACUGUUAAAUCCACUUUGCUGUAGGUUAUAGUUUACCUGUUAUAUAAUUCGUAGUGCUAAUUGUAGUAGAAGCAAAUCAAUUUAGGAUGUUGGAACGAAAAUAAUCACAAUAACUAAUACAGCUUUUUAAUUGUGAAAACUACAAUUAAAAAUUAUAAUUUUAAUACCAACCAUAAUAUUACACUGUAUUUAGAACAGGCUUAUGUAAAAUGCCCUCAUUUAUCUAAAUAAGUUGAUUUUUUGGUUAUUGUAAUCUAGUAAGGUUUUUGCAUCACUACUGGUCUGUCAUGAAGUUUUUCUGCUGGCUUAUUCACUUAUUUAGACUUCAUUUAGGGAAGCUAUUUCAGAAUACCAUCUCAUAAAAUGUAUCAUUAUCUUGUUUUUGCAAAAUUCACUUACUUUUUGGGCACAUUUACCCAGCAUUUCAAAUAAGUGUAUAGGCAUGUGCCUUGUUUAAGUACAAUUUAUAAGACUUCAUGUUUGCAAGUUACAUAUUAGGGUAGUGAUUGUUUAUAUUACCAGGGAUUCUACACUUUACCAAAAAAAAUUGCCAUAAGAUUUUCCUGUUCCAUUUUAAAUUGUCUUGAUAUUUAAAAAAAUAACUUCUACAUUCUCAGGAAGAAAUACAUGAAGUAAAUCAUAUCUCCAUGUCUGUUUCCAGAUUUCUCUAAUCUUUUUACUAUCCCAAUACAUUCCUAAUUCCUAUAAACGUAGUGGCUUAAAUACUGAAUACCUGGCAGCUCUUAAAGAUCCCUUAGGCAGAUGAUGAUAAUUUUCAGUGUUUCGUCAUGUUUAAUAGAAAUCAAACUGACUUGUGUUUUAAAAUACAAGUUGUCUGCUAGUAAAGUUACAUGAUUUAGGUGUGUUUUAGGUUUUCUGCAACAAUUAGCUGUGAACCCCUAAUGUAGCUAAGUUUAUACAAAUUUUAUAAUCAAAAUUAUUUAUUUUUAUUUUUUUAGAGUAUGUCAAAAACAUAUAGUGUUUGCUUUGUGAAAUACAUUUGCUUAGAGUUAUAAAAUAUACUGUGACUCAGAAAUUGUAAAGUCAGUUUGCGUUGUAAAAAUGAAUACUACCAGCAUGUCAAAAGAAAAAUAAUUUACAUUUGUAAUAUAAAGUAAAAUUGUAUUUAAUAUAUUUAUUGAAUUUUAAAUUUGCACUAACUUGAAAACUUUAAAGGUUAUACUAAUUUAAUGAUUAAUGUGGACCCAAAUACAUAAUUUGGCCAAAAAAGUCAUUAGAAUGGGUAAUGGUUUUGUGUGGUUUUCCUUCAAAAUGAUAAUAUUGAAGCAAGAACCAGCAUUUUAUAUUGAUAAUUUUUUUAAUAUUUCUACCCAGUUGAGGACAGUGGAAUAUAAGUAGAUAUAUUUAAAAUAUCUAGAUAUUUAAAAAGAAAGAAAAGGUUGUUUAUCCCAAUCUGAAUUCAUUCUCAGCAACAAGACAGAAAAGGUGGUUUGGGUUUUGCUUUUAAACAGUGUCCCCCUGUCUUUUUCAAUUUUUCCCUUGAAGCCUUUCUCUUGUUCUUCAGAGUACGCGCUGCAGGCUAUCUGCAGCAUCAGAAUGCCUGGGCAGGCUGUUGAAAGUAUGGAUUCCUGAGCCCAACCCUUAACUUAAUGAUUCCCUGUCUCUGGAGAUGCAACAUAGAAAUCUCUGUUUUUAUUAACAAGCGCCUCAGGCGAUUCUUAAGCAUACUGAAAUUUGAAAGCUUCUGGUCUGAACCUCAUGUAUUCACCUAGGGCUUUUGCUAGGUGGGAUACCAUGCCGAAAAAUUGAAUUAAUUGUAUGUUCUUAAAAUUGUUUUUCUUCUACUCCGCUGUCCUCUUCCCUCAAAAUCACUUUUCUAAAAGAACUCUAUGAAAAACUUAUUUGUAUCAUACCCAAAUUGAUAUAUUUGUCUGAACUCUGUUACAUAAAAAUUGGUAUGAUUCAUAUGUGGAAUCAGUUUUUGGACUGUGACCCAUGCAGUGUUGGGGGACAAGGAGUUGCUUCAGGAGUUAGUGCAGUGCGCCUCCAAGGGGCAGUGAGCCAUGGAGGCGCCUGCCUUCUCACUGCAGUCAAUGCAGCCACACUUGUGUAUACUGAGUGCUGCUUCAGAUCUCAGUAGAUAAAAUAAUUCCACAUUUAAAAUGAUUCUGCUAUUUUUUAUAAAGGGUUUGAAAGCCACUACUAUAAUGACUUUGUCACCUAAUUGAUUUUCUACUAAUUUUUACAUAUUCAGAAACUUCGUGUUUUUUUGGUGGACAGAAUAUUUUGGAGGUCUCCGUCGCUGUUUAGAAUGUGGCCACUUGGCUGUUUCACAGUUUUUAAAGCUAUUUUAUUGAAUAGUAAAGCAGUGAACUUAGCCUUUGUUCUUUGUGUUUCUAAUUUAAGCAUAUAGUCUAUUUAAUUUUUGAUAUGUAAAUACACAUCAAUACAUAUAUAUUUACCCAUGUGGCCCUGUGUAGUCAGUGCAUGAGGCUUGCAUAGCCCAGAAAGGUACAUUCCAGGGUUCUGGGGAAAGAAUUUUAAAAUGCCAUCCUCUAAUACAGACGUUUAUAAAACUUAAAUGAAAUGAUUGGGCUUAACCAUAUGCAAGAAAGUCUGCAGAAAAUAAAUCACCUAGAAACUAUAAAUAGAAAUGUGCUGCUGAGGCUGGGCACGGUGGCUCACACCUGUAAUCCCAGCACUUGGGGGGCUAAGGGAGGCGUAUCACCUGAGGUCAGGAGUUUGAGACAAGCCUGGUCAACAUGGUGAAACGCCGUCUCUACUAAAAAUACAAAAAAAAUUAGCCAGGUACAUUGGCACAUGCCUUUAAUCCCAGCUAAUCAGGAGGCUGAGGCACGAGAAUUGCUCGAACCCAGGCGGCAGAGCUUGCAGUGAGCGGAGAUCACAUGACUGCACUCCAGCCUGGGCAACAGAGCAAGACUCCAUCUCAAAAAAAAAAAGGCCGGGCGUGGUGGCUCACGCCUGUAAUCCCAGCACUUUGGGAGGCUGAGGCAGGUGGAUCACGAGGUCAGGAGAUCGAGACUAUCCUGGCUAACACGGUGACACCCCGCCUCUACUAAAAAUCCAAAAAUUUAGCCGGGCAUGGUGGCGGGCACCUGUAGUCCCAGCUACUCGGGAGGCUGAGGCAGGAGAAUGGCGUGAACCCGGGAGGCAGAGCUUGCAGGGAGGCGGAGCUUGCAGCGAGCCGAGAUAGUGCCACUGCAGUGGGGCCUGGGCCAAAGAGUGAGACUCCAUCUCAAAAAAAAAAAAAAAGAAAGAAAUGUGUUGCUGGUAUCAGAUAUCAGACCAAGAACACUUCAGUCUCUCUAAGGAUGCCCUGAGCUACCUCACUGUUAAAGGACGACAUCAACACAGAAUGCACUAAACAGGAAAUAAGCUGUAAUCUAGAGAAUUUCCAUUAUGUGUUACUUUUUGGUGACUAACAUGGAAUGUUGAAAAGGAAGAGCUGGAAAGCUCAGUUGUUUUCCUUGUUCCUCUGACAUUGUCCAGGCAAGAGGGCAUCCUGAUCAGAUGAGUAGAUUUGGCUGAGAAAAACCCUAGAGUAAGGCAGGCACUUUGUGGAGGUGGAUGAUGAUGGCUCAUAAAAACGUUUGUUCUCAGUCCAGUUCAGGGCUCUGCCAGCAGUCUUUCAGAUCUGAACUGCUUAAACAAACCCUACAGAUAAAUUGGCACUCUGAUUUGUAAUUCUGUUUGUACAAGUUUAGAGCAGCCUAGCUCGAGUCCUCAACCCCAGUCCUCUUAGAAGUGAACUGAUUGCACUGGAUCCCUAAACCCACAAUGUUGAGGACACAUGUGAUGACUCCACUUGCUCAGCCAGCUGGCCUCUUGCACUUUCCCCUGCCCACCACUUGUAACUACCACUUAAUUAUCUUGUGUUAAUUGCUUUUGUUGUGUUGGGUCUGUAUUUUUGUGGUCAGUGCCUGCAGGCAGAAAUGUGAAAGCAUUUGGUAUGUUGAAGAUACUUGCUUCUUUUUUAAUAAAAUUAAAAGUGCAGCACGUAAGUAUGAUACUGUGUAGUUUUUUGACACAACCAUGAGAUACAAUAAGCAGCUUUGACUUAGUGUCCCAAAAAGUGGUUCUUGGUCUACAGCAGGGCAAACAUAUAUGUGGCAAGUUCUGAUCACAUACUUUUAGACAGAAAGAAUAAAAAAUUCAUAUUGCAUGGCUUUUGUAGCCUAAGAGCACAGAAUCAUACACGUGUGUUAGGAGAAACAUUCAUUCUCACGCAUAUAAACUGGCUCCUGGCAGAGUAGAGCAGUAAGUGGGAUCAAAGGUGAAUUCACCUUAUUUUCAGUUGGUAGAGUAUGGAAAAAUGUAUCACUUAUUUGAAAUACCUGAAUGGAAACCCAGCCUCUACUACUGUAACUUAACACUUGUUCUUCCUGAGCCUCAAAUUUUCUUUCUCUGUAAGAAUGGGAAUUAAUGCCCACCUACGGGUUGCAAGUGCUUACAGGAGCUGGGCAAGCAACGAAGGUAAGAGUUGUAGAGACUUCGGUAAACUGGAGCACAUGAUUCCUGGGAAGCAGGCCUAGUGUAAACAAUUUAUUUUUCUAGAAAAGACAGAAGUUUAGAGUAUAUGAAAUCUAAUUUUUAAGUAUUGGUUGGCAACUAAUUGACUAUCGUCUACCAUAAGGUUAUAUGAUAAUUAUUAGGGCAGGAGAGUGAAUGCAUCUUAAUAUGCAUGGCAGAACUGUGUGUUUCCUUCCAUCUGGAUUUUCAUAAAGCUUUCUGAUUUAUCAGUAACGAUCUGAAAAAUGUACUGUGGCAUGUAACAUCUUUUAUUCAUUUUAUUAGGCAUUAGAGGAAGAAUAUUCUGUAGUCCUGCUUUAUUCUGCCAUCUUUACCUGGAAAUCCAUUUUUAUAAAAUUUUUGUAAUAAAAAUUCACUUGAUCA